CUUUCCGGGUCCUUGCACGCUUCGCUCCAACUCCUGCAGAGCUGAGCCGGAGGGGAAUCCGGAAGGGACACGCUGAACAGGAACAGAAAUGAAUAAAAGUCGCUGGCAGAGUAGAAGACGACAUGGGAGAAGAAGCCACCAGCAGAACCCUUGGUUCAGACUCCGUGAUUCUGAAGACAGGUCUGACUCCCGGGCAGCACAGCCCGCUCACGAUUCCGGCCACGGUGAUGACGAGUCUCCGUCAACCUCGUCUGGCACAGCUGGGACCUCCUCUGUGCCAGAGCUACCUGGGUUUUACUUUGACCCUGAAAAGAAACGCUACUUCCGCUUGCUCCCUGGACAUAACAACUGCAACCCCCUGACGAAAGAGAGCAUCCGGCAGAAGGAGAUGGAGAGCAAGAGACUGCGGCUGCUCCAGGAAGAAGACAGACGGAAAAAGAUUGCCAGGAUGGGAUUUAAUGCAUCUUCCAUGCUACGAAAAAGCCAGCUGGGUUUUCUCAACGUCACCAAUUACUGCCAUUUAGCCCACGAGCUGCGUCUCAGCUGCAUGGAGAGGAAAAAGGUCCAGAUUCGAAGCAUGGAUCCCUCCGCCUUGGCAAGCGACCGAUUUAACCUCAUACUGGCAGAUACCAACAGUGACCGGCUCUUCACAGUGAACGAUGUUAAAGUUGGAGGCUCCAAGUAUGGUAUCAUCAACCUGCAAAGUCUGAAGACCCCUACGCUCAAGGUGUUCAUGCACGAAAACCUCUACUUCACCAACCGGAAGGUGAAUUCGGUGUGCUGGGCCUCGCUGAAUCACUUGGAUUCCCACAUUCUGCUAUGCCUCAUGGGACUCGCAGAGACUCCAGGCUGUGCCACCCUGCUCCCAGCAUCACUGUUCGUCAAUAGUCACCCAGGAAUAGACCGGCCUGGCAUGCUCUGCAGUUUCCGGAUCCCUGGUGCCUGGUCCUGUGCCUGGUCCCUGAAUAUCCAAGCAAAUAACUGCUUCAGUACAGGCUUGUCUCGGCGGGUCCUGUUGACCAACGUGGUGACGGGACACCGGCAGUCCUUUGGGACCAACAGUGAUGUCUUGGCCCAGCAGUUUGCUCUCAUGGCUCCUCUGCUGUUUAAUGGCUGCCGCUCUGGGGAAAUCUUUGCCAUUGAUCUGCGUUGUGGAAAUCAAGGCAAGGGAUGGAAGGCCACCCGCCUGUUUCAUGAUUCAGCAGUGACCUCUGUGCGGAUCCUCCAAGAUGAGCAAUACCUGAUGGCUUCAGACAUGGCUGGAAAGAUCAAGCUGUGGGACCUGAGGACCACGAAGUGCGUAAGGCAGUACGAAGGCCACGUGAAUGAGUACGCCUACCUGCCCCUGCAUGUGCACGAGGAAGAAGGAAUCCUGGUGGCAGGAUCAUGGUGGCACAGGAAGGGAUGGCUGGAUAGUAGAAUGCAUCCUCCACAUCUUCAGGAAAGGACAGAGAUACCUCAACAGGAGAAGUUGGGCAGAGACAGGCAAGUGCUGCCUCCAUUUCCAGCCUCAUGAUGGUUCCUGGGCCAUAGCAAAGCCUGGUUGAGGGGAAGAGGCCCAGGGACUGCAUCUUUCCAGCUUUUCUUCACAUACACAAGCAGAUGGUGGCACAGUACUCCCUGAUACUAGCUAAUAAGCACCUACUGUAUGUCAGGCCCCCCCCACCUUUUUUUUUUUUUGAGACAUGGUCUCACUCUGUCGCCCAAGCUGGAGUGCAUGAGUUGCAGUAGCACAAUUACUACUCACUGCAGUCUUGACCUCCUUGGGCUUGAGCAAUCCUCCCACCUCAGUCUUCUGAGCAGUUGGGCCCACAGGUGUGCACCACCACACUCAGUUAAUUUUUUAUUUUUUGUAGAGAUGGCGUCUCCCUAUGUUUCCCAGGCUGGUCUUGAACUCCUAGGCUCAAGUGAUCCUCUGGCCUCAGCCUCCCAAAGUGCUGGCAUUACAGACACGAGCCAUUUGUAAGACACUUCUCACCCUCACACUAACCCCACGGCACAGUUUGGGAAACAAGUUUGUUGAGUUAAAGUGGUUUGGCAAGAAGGGCUGAGCUGGGAUUAAGAUUCCGCUCUUCCCAACUCUGAAGCCCCUGUUCCCCUCACUGCUGUGUCCUGCUCAUUUUCCAGGCCCAGGUUAACAACAAUGGGAAAGAGUUGAGAGAUACUUUUCUAACAGGGUAAACCCUCCUCCCAGCCCAACUCCACCAUCCUGGGCCACUCCUCUACUCACAUGAUCCUUUGUACCAUUUGGUCCAAUUGAUCUUGAUCUCAUCCAUUUUUUCCACAUGGGUCAGAGACAAGGGUGAGAUUUUUCUCAUUUCUCGUGGGAGAAAGGCAAGCUCUGCCAAGCCCAGAAUUUCUGGCCCCUCCUGUCCCAGCACAAACCAUUCACAGUCUUCCCGCAAUUAUUCCUGGUGCAGGGUUUUAUUUCUAGGAAGCCUUCUGUCCCUCAACCUCACCAGCCCUUGGCUUUUCAGCCCAGAGGCUCAGGACAUUUGAGGAUUGCGUGUUUGGCUGUGGGCAUGGGGAAUGCAGUGACUACACCUGGUUGGCAUCCCAUACCACACCCAGGGGAAUGGGGAAGCCAAGAGGUGGACUGGAAGCAGGCUCAGGCCUCUCUCUCCUUGCCCCCAAGGGCAUCCUCUCCAGCAGAUGGCCACUACAAUGCUGAUGUCAAACUGGUCAGUGGGUUCAGUGGAAGGUUUGGCUACCGCGGGAACACCCCAGCUCUCCGUCGGAGCACGUCUGUCUUUGGAGAGGUCACCCACUUCCCUCUGUUCUAACAGCAUCUCUUCCCUUCAUAGCCCUCAACCUGAAUUUCUAAGACAGAUGUUUAGGUGAACUCUCAAUGUUAUUUUACAUUAAAAAAAUUUGUGUCUCCAA